AUGAAUGCUGGCUUUCAGAGAGAACAGCGUUUCAGUUUUGGUCAUCGGAAGUGGUGCCUUCAGCACAG